GUGCAACCCGAACGGCGUCGGGCCGUGGAAGCUGCGCUGCUUGGCGCAGACCUUCGCCACCGGUGAGCGGGGGAAACUGAGGCACGAGGGACAAGAGGUCGUCGGGGAGUGAAAGCAGGCGCAGGGAAAUAAAAAGAAGGAAAGGGAGACAGACCAGGCGCCUAACAGAUGGGGACCAAGAAACAAGAGAUAGCUGAGAGGUGCAAACAGAAGAGAAAAAAGAGCAACAUCCCUUAGGAGAGGGGCAGAGGAGAGAGAGGUGGAGAGAGGGGGCGGAGAGUGCUCAGAAUUGAGAGCUAAGGUGGGGGAUGCAGGACAGACUGAGGUGGAGAUGCAUAGGAGGAAAUGGAGGCAGAUGUGGGACAGGGGUGAGAAACUGCCAGGAUUUCCUCGCUGAGCCUGGCUGGUGAAGUGUCCGGACGCACCCUCAUCGACAUUGGUUCAGGCCCCACCGUGUACCAGCUGCUCAGUGCCUGCAGCCACUUUGAGGACAUCACCAUGACAGAUUUCCUGGAGGUCAACCGCCAGGAGCUGGGGCGCUGGCUGCAGGAGGAGCCGGGGGCCUUCAACUGGAGCAUGUACAGCCAACAUGCCUGCCUCAUUGAGGGCAAGGGGGAAUGCUGGCAGGAUAAGGAGCGCCAGCUGCGAGCCAGGGUGAAACGGGUCCUGCCCAUCGACGUGCACCAGCCCCAGCCCCUGGGUGCUGGGAGCCCAGCUCCCCUGCCUGCUGACGCCCUGGUCUCUGCCUUCUGCUUGGAGGCUGUGAGCCCAGAUCUUGCCAGCUUUCAGCGGGCCCUGGACCACAUCACCACGCUGCUGAGGCCUGGGGGGCACCUCCUCCUCAUCGGGGCCCUGGAGGAGUCGUGGUACCUGGCUGGGGAGGCCAGGCUGACGGUGGUGCCAGUGUCUGAGGAGGAGGUGAGGGAGGCCCUGGUGCGUAGUGGCUACAAGGUCCGGGACCUCCGCACCUAUAUCAUGCCUGCCCACCUUCAGACAGGCGUAGAUGAUGUCAAGGGCGUCUUCUUCGCCUGGGCUCAGAAGGUUGGGCUGUGAGGGCUGUACCUGGUGCCCUGUGGCCCCCACCCACCUGGAUUCCCUGUUCUUUGAAGUGGCACCUAAUAAAGAAAUAAUACCCUGCC